AGCCUCCCCAGUAGCUGGGAUUACAGACACGUGCCACCGCGCCCAGCUAAUUUUUGUAUUUUUAGUAGAGCUGAGGUUUCACAAGUUUCACAAGUUGCCCAGCCUGGUCUUGAACUCCUGACCUCAUGAUCCAUCCGCCUCGGCCUCCCAAAGUGCUGGGAUUAUAGGCAUGAGCCACCGCACCCGGCCAGCUAAAGGUUUUUUAAAUAUUGUUUUGGUAGAGACAAGGUCUUAUUAUGUUGCCCAGUCUGGUCUCCAACUCGUUGGGCUCAAGCAAUCCUCCUGCCUCAGCUUCCCAAAGUGCUAAGAUUACAGGUGGCAGCCACCAUGCCUGGCCAAGAAGGAAACUUUAAAACAGGUGUCAAGGACAGCAAGGAUUUGAAUAAUUAGCUUAGUACACAGAGGGCUCACUACAUAUCUAAAUUUGCACCGAACAGAGGAUAAAAUUAUGUUGUUUCUGAAACACUUUUAAAAAUCGAUCAUGUACCAGACCACAAAGAAAAAUAUGAACUCUUAAAAGUAGAAAUCAUAACAGGCCACAUCUUGUUAAUGUAAUGCAUUAAACUUGAAAUUAACUACAAAAAGCUUCUCCCCCACCAAAAAAGAACUAACCCCCUGGAAAUUUUAAACUAUUUUUUAAAUAGCCUUUAGACUAAAGAAAUUAAUAGAACACUUUAUCAAAGUAUAUGGGAUUUGGCCAAAGCUUUAUUUAAAGAAAAAUAUAUAGCCUUACAUAUUUUUAUUAACAGCCAGAAGAUAUUGCAAAUAAGCACCUAACUCAAGAAACCAGAAAAAGGGCCUAGUGGAGUGGGUCACGCCUGCAGAUCUAGCUACCUGGCAGGCUGACACAAGAGGAUCACUUGAGGCUUCAGUGAGCUAUGAUCCAGCCUGGGCAACAGAGCGAGUCUGGGGGAGAAAAAAAAGAUAAAGAACAAAAUAAAUCAGAAGAAUGUAGGAACAAGGAGUUAAUAAGGAUAGAAGUAGACACUAAUGAAUUAGCACAUUAAAAAACAUAAAUGAUAAAAUUAAAACAUUAUUUAAAAUGUAAAUGUAUAACAUUACAAAAUAUGAAAGGCUAUAGGCACUAAUAUGGAGAUCUUUAAAGUUAUAAAGACAUUUAAUGUUCAAGUUUAGGCCAAAUAAAUGUGAAAAUCUGAGAAAAAUAGGUGAUUUUUUAAAGGAAAAUACAAACCACCAAACUUGAAGCACAGUUAGAAAACUUGUAUAAAUCAGUAACUAAAAAGAAAUUGAAAAGAUUGUCAAAGAUAGACUACCUUCAUCCCACCUAUUCCCAUAUUCCUGUAUGAGUUUAAAUUUGAAUUCCUCUUUAGGGACAAGUUAAAUCUCAUUAAUGAGUUUUGUAGUAUACUUAAGAUUCUACAUUAAGUCAGAGGGGGUGAAGUUUGGAUUUGAUUUUUAUUAUUAAACAGCCAGUUUUUUAAGUUCAGGGGUACAUGUGCAGGAUGUGCAGGUUUUGUUACAUAAGUAAAUGUGUGUCAUAGGGGUUUGUUGUAUAGAUUAUUUCAUCACCCAGGUAUUAAGCCUAGUGUCCCUUAGUUAUUUUUCCUGAUCCUUUCCCUCCUGCCACCCUUCAUCCUUCCAUAUACCCUUCACCCUUCCAUAUACCCCAGUGUGUGUUCCCCUCUAUGUGUCCGUGUGCUGUCAUCAUUUAGUUCCCACUUAUUAGUGAGAACAUGCAGUAUUUGGUUUUCUGUUCCUACAUUAGUUUGCUAAAGAUAAUGGUCUCCAGCUCCAUCCAUGUCCCUGCAAAGGACAUGAUCUCCUUUUUUAUGGCUGUAUAGUAUUUCAUGGUGUAUACUGGAAAAUACAUUUUCUUUAUCCAGUCUACCAUUGAUGGGCAUUUAGGUUGAUUCCAUGUCUUUGCUAUUGUGAAUAGCACUGCAAUGAACAUAAGUGUGGAUGUGUCUUUAUAAUAGAACAAUUUAUAUUCCUUUGGGUAUAUACCCAGUAAUGGGAUUGCUGGGUCAAAUGGUAAUUCUGUCUUUAGGUCUUUGAGGAAUUGUCACACUGCCUUCCUCAAUGGUGAACUGAUUUAUACUCCAACCAAGAGUUUAAAAGCUUUCCUUUGCCUCCACAACCUUGCCAGUAUCUGUUAUUUUUUGACUUUUGAAUAAUAGCCAUUCUGACUGAUAUGAGAUGGUAUCUCAUUAUGGUUUUGAUUUGCAUUUCUCUAAUCAGUGAAGCUGACCUUUUUUUCACAUGAUUGUUGGCCACAGGUAUGUCUUGUUUUGAGAAGUGUCUUUGCCUACUUUUAAGUGGGGUUUGAACAGGCAUUUAUUAAACAUCCAGCAUAAGUAAAAUUGCAUUAAAUGCUGAUGGGGGGGAGAUAUAAAUAAUAAGAGACAAACCUAUCUUCAAAAAGACUAGUAAUGUGAAAUAAACAUUUGCAUGAAACAGUAGGAUUGAAGAAUAAGAACAAAAGAGCACUACGUGUGAGAAGCUCACUUGAAAGUCCCAAAUUGAAAUAAACACUGUUUUGAUGAGAAGGGGCCUCCUUUUUAAUAUUCUUUCCAUGUGGAAUCAUCAGCAGUAAAGAGAUCUAUAGAUCUGGAAGCAGAAGAGCUGGCUGGAUGGAGGGGACUUUGCUGACAUCCCCUCUGAAAAAUAAGCUCGAGAGUCAGGAUGUCUCAGAUUUAACAACAGUUGAAAGGGAAGACUCAUCAUUACUUAAUCCUGCAGCCAAAAAACUGAAAAUAGAUACCAAAGAAAAGAAAGAGAAAAAGCAGAAAGUAGAUGAAGAUGAGAUUCAGAAGAUGCAAAUCCUGGUUUCUUCUUUUUCUGAGGAGCAGCUGAACCGUUAUGAAAUGUAUCGCCGCUCAGCUUUCCCUAAGGCAGCCAUCAAAAGGCUGAUCCAGUCCAUCACUGGCACCUCUGUGUCUCAGAAUGUUGUUAUUGCUAUGUCUGGUAUUUCCAAGGUUUUCGUCGGGGAGGUGGUAGAAGAAGCACUGGAUGUGUGUGAGAAGUGGGGAGAAAUGCCACCACUACAACCCAAACAUAUGAGGGAAGCCGUUAGAAGGUUAAAGUCAAAAGGACAGAUCCCUAACUCGAAGCACAAAAAAAUCAUCUUCUUCUAGACCAAAGUCUAGAAAGGCCUAUGUUACUGACGGAAGAAGUAUUGGUUCCAGACUUCCUAUAAGACUGUCUGCAUUGGUGCUUUAGUAUCUCAGGCCUCCAAGGAUUCCAUGAUGAUUUUAAUGUCUUUCUCAAAACUCUGAUAUUUGUCACACCUAGAAAGUAUGUAGCCUGAUUGAUACUUGCCUUGACUAAAUUUUGGGACCUCUUGGGGCAUUUUGAAGUAUUUAACUGUCUUGACCAGUUGGAAGAAGAUACGUGGGCCAUAAGCAUCUUCUGGACAGGGGAACUGCUUUCAGAGAGAAAACCUUUCCAAGAGAGUUUUGUUUUGUUUUGGUUUCGUUUUGUUUGAGAUAGGGUCUUGCUCUAUCACCUAGGCUGGAGUGCAGCGGCAUGACUGCAGCCUUGAACUCCUGGGCUUAAGUGACCCUCCCACCUCAGUCUCCUGAGUAGCUAGGACUACAGGCACACACUACUGUGCCCAGCUAACUUAUUUUUAUUUUUUAUGGAGAUGGGGUCUUGCUUUGUUGCCCAGGCUGGUCGUGAACUCCUGGCUUCAAGCAGUCCUCCUGCCUCAGCCUCCUAAAGUGCUGAGGGCUUUAAUGGUUUCACAUUGAAGCCUGAAGUUGCUAAGACUUAGGUUGUUUCUUAUAUCUGGUUUUAAGUAGAUGAAACAACCAGAAACUUUUACUUGUGAUACUCUACCAUGAAGGAUGCGGUAAUGGCAGGAAUAGCAGAAUAAUUGGUGCUUGUAAACAUUUAAGAUUCUCCUGUGGAUUUUGGUGAGUGAUCAUUAAACUGUUUUCCAACUUGCCCUAGGUGUAUUCAUUUUCUGUCUAGCUGGUUGGAAUGGGAAGUUGAUCAUUCUUUUUUGGUGUUCCAAUACAACUGGUUUUGGCUAUUUUGUGAAAAUUUGAGCACUUUUUCUAGUAGAACCAUUAAAAUUUUAUCUCAUAAAAGAGUACUUCAAGCACUGUUAAAAACAGUGUAAUAAUUCCCCCCCCAAGACUGAGAUGAAAAUAAACAAUAUAAAAGCCCAUAUAUUUCAGAUUCUUAUCAACGGAUAUACAACAAUCAUUAUGGUUUAAUACAUUUAAUUUGUUUUUUCAGGUGGUUCACAGAACCAGUAC